CCCUGAGUAGCUGCUCCGGGAGCUGUGGUGCCCUCUCCUUCUCCCUUUGGCUCCUCUCCUGCUGCCUUACAGUGCCCCCAGAGCCGGCUAGGGGCAUGGACUUCACCUCCUGGUCCUCUCUUCCUCAGGUAUGGCGUUGACGGUGGAUGUGGCCGGGCCAGCGCCCUGGGGCUUCCGUAUCACAGGGGGCAGGGAUUUCCACACGCCCAUCAUGGUGACUAAGGUGGCCGAGCGGGGCAAAGCCAAGGACGCUGACCUCCGGCCUGGAGACAUAAUCGUGGCCAUCAACGGGGAAAGCGCGGAGGGCAUGCUGCAUGCCGAGGCCCAGAGCAAGAUCCGCCAGAGCCCCUCGCCCCUGCGGCUGCAGCUGGACCGGUCUCAGGCUACGUCUCCAGGGCAGACCAAUGGGGACAGCUCCUUGGAAGUGCUGGCGACUCGCUUCCAGGGCUCCGUGAGGACAUACACUGAGAGUCAGUCCUCCUUAAGGUCCUCCUACUCCAGCCCAACCUCCCUCAGCCCGAGGGCCGGCAGCCCCUUCUCACCACCACCCUCUAGCAGCUCCCUCACUGGAGAGGCAGCCAUCAGCCGCAGCUUCCAGAGUCUGGCAUGUUCCCCGGGCCUCCCCGCUGCUGACCGCCUGUCCUACUCAGGCCGCCCUGGAAGCCGACAGGCCGGCCUCGGCCGCGCUGGCGACUCGGCGGUGCUGGUGCUGCCGCCUUCCCCGGGCCCUCGUUCCUCCAGGCCCAGCAUGGACUCGGAAGGGGGAAGCCUCCUCCUGGACGAGGACUCGGAAGUCUUCAAGAUGCUGCAGGAAAAUCGCGAGGGACGGGCGGCCCCCCGACAGUCCAGCUCCUUUCGGCUCUUGCAGGAAGCCCUGGAGGCUGAGGAGAGAGGUGGCACGCCAGCCUUCUUGCCCAGCUCACUGAGCCCCCAGUCCUCCCUGCCCGCCUCCAGGGCCCUGGCCACCCCUCCCAAGCUCCACACUUGUGAGAAGUGCAGUACCAGCAUCGCGAACCAGGCUGUGCGCAUCCAGGAGGGCCGGUACCGCCACCCCGGCUGCUACACCUGUGCCGACUGUGGGCUGAACCUGAAGAUGCGCGGGCACUUCUGGGAGGACGCUUGUGCUAUGGAGGGAAUGAGAUUGUCACUGGAAGCUUUGGAGGGGAUGGUGGAGGGCGCCAAGCGGAGGGACAGGAGGAAGACCAGGAGACCCAUCCAGCCAAGCUGGUGAGACAACCUCUGAUCCUGAGGACCGGCCGCCCACCAAGGGUUGGGCCCCCGGGGCCAGGUUGAUCUACCGACACCUUCCACUUCUUUCCUGGGAGAGACUGCUGGCUUCAUUGGUGAUUGAUUUGGAGGGGGGAAAAAGGGCAGGGUGGCUCAGGCUUUAGGCCCAGGUACUGGGGAGGCCUGAGGAGCCCUCCUGGAGCUCAGGAGGCCGAGGCUGCCUUAAGCUGUGAUCAUGCCACUGCAUUCCAGCCUGGGAGAGAGAGAGGACCUGUCUGUUGAAAAAAACACAAAAACAAAUGAAUGCAUGUGGCCAGUGCCAGGUGAGCUGCCCUGGGGGUUCACUGGAGUUGAGGCAGGGGACAGUAGUCUCCCCUGCCAGCCUAGGAUUUUGGGCGUCAUUCACCCACUACCCCUAGUGCUAGUCCCAGAGGAUGCUGCGGAGGGGGCAGCCUCAGCUCUCUUUUCAGAGAAGAUCAAAGCUGGGCUUCCCAGGGUGCCUGGCUGGUCCCUGCCGGCAGCUUUGUGCUCUCCGGCUCUUUGUGAAAGGAAUCUUGGCGCAGAUGUUUGUGUUGCCUCCUCAGGCACCUGUAGAUAUAAUUUACACCAUGAUAUCAUUGUCUCACCUUUUGCCUGGGUGGCUGCCUGAGAAAGGUCUUUCUUUUUAUAGAAAAGAUCAAGGCUGUCUGGCGCGGGACUCCAUGAGCCCCAGGCGCUGGUCAGAAACGGGGUAGUCUCUUUGGCGCCACCUAGUGUCCAGUUUGGCCCAUGGCGGGGCCCAUUCACGGGGCAACACUGGGCUUCUGGGCACAGCGGGAAUACAGAAAGAUACAGCACUCCUCAUGCCUUCCUGGAGGUAGAAGGCCAGUGGCAGCGACUGAGCUGGCAUGAAUGAAUAAGAGGAUGUGGCACUGAGCGCCAAGGGCUACCUUGGAACGCACCGAGGAGCGUCCCGUGAGUUCAAAGCAGUGGCCGUGAUGCAAAAGGAGGGCUGGGUCUUGGAGACGUGGAGAAGAGGAAUGCUGAGUGAUGGGGUGGCUGCUGGGGGGAUGCUUAGCUCAGAGCAGUGGCUGAUGGGGACACUGAGAUAAGAUCGGAGGGGAGCUGUCAAUGCCAGAAGUGGUUUGAACUUCCCCUUGAGGCUCUAGGGACAUUUUGUUUUGAGACAUGGUCUUGCUCUAUUGCCCAGGCUGGAGUGCAGUGGUACAAUCUUAGCUCACUGCAGCCUCCACCUCCCAGGCUCAAGAGAUCCUCCCACAGCCUCCCAGGUAGCUGGGACUACAGGCGUGCACCACCACACCCAGCUAAUUUUUAAGUUUUUUUUUUUUUUUAAGAGAUGGGGUCUCACUAUGUUGCCCAGGCUGGUCUCGAACUUCGGGCCCCAAGCCAUCCUCCCACCUUGGCUUUCCAAAGUGUUGGGAUUACAAGCGUGAGCUAACCUUGCCCAGCCUCUGGGAACACUUGGAAGGUUUUAAGCAGAGAAGUGACAGGUUGGAAAAGAUGGUUUGGAUUAUUGAUAUGGACAGAUUCCCACCUGUAUGUAGCACGCCAUGCUGGGCCAGCAGUGUCAUAGGAGUGGAGGGGGAUAAGUGGGGACUGGGGACAUGUGAAAUGAUGGGCAUUCCAGUGAGGCAUCGAAUGCCUUCUGAGGGCUUUGUAGGUUCCAGCUCAAAUCCCCCUCUGGCUCUUGUUCUUUGGUGUGGCAGCCAUCUCUCCUCCCAGGGGUCCUGAGGGUUUCAGCACCAGGGUUCUCUGCAGCCACACAAUCAGCCCGGCUCGGGAGCAAACUCCCCUGGAAGAACGGAGUUAUGAGUUGGUCAGCAGAGGAGGCUGGGGACAGGCAGUUUUUGGUCUUUUACCUCUGAUCUUGUCCCCAACCUAAGCCAGCUAGCUGCGUGCUCCCACUCCCUCUGCCGCACGCCGCCCGUCUAUGUUCCCGGACUUUGUCCAGUGCAGUGCCCUCUUCCCUUCCUGCACUGAGGAGAUUAACUGAAGUGACAGAUUAGAGUUAGAAGUGGCCCAAAGGAGCAUCUGGUACAACCCCCUUUGGUUAGAGAAGGGAAAGUGACUUUUCCAAAGCUGCACAGCUAGACAGUCAUAAUGGCUAAGCUCUGGGGGUGCUUUUGAUGUGCUAGGGAUACUUCCAAUGCUUUAACUCACUUAAUCCUCACAACCCGAGAUAGGUACUGUUACCAUCCUCUCUGCAGACGAGGAAACCGAGGACCAGGAGGUUCAGUAAAUGGUCCAAGUACUCCUAGCUAGUAAGGAAUGGAUCUACAGCCUGCCUCCCAGGUUUCUGGCUUGUGGGGGGCAGAGUUUGUCCCUCUGUCAUCAGAGGCAGCCUUCCAGGCACAGCUCUGGUCACCUCUGGUCACAACUGGAGGUCACCACAGCCCUCCCCAGCGCUCUGUAGGCUCUCAGCUUUGUGCUUCCUCCCACGGGUACUAGCUCCAGCUGAGCUUGCAGGAAACCCACUUCCUGAAGCCAGGACUUCCCCAUGGGAAGUGCAGGGGCCACUGGGCAGCCUGAGGGCUGACCCUGCUCAGGACACUGUCUGUCUCAGGAACUCAUGGCAGUGGUUUACCUUGUCAGGAGUGCAUGGACGGGCUGCCCCUCCCAUUCCUUCAAGCAUCACUCAGAGAGCCCUGGCCUGGCUCUAGGCUUGGGACUGCGGCUGCCACAGGAAGGGGGCAUCCCCCUACUUUGGGUGUUGGGUCAGAUCCUGCCCCCGUGCCCGCCAGGGCUCAGGUUCCUCUGAGCUGGUCCUGGGCCAGGACGCAUCUGCAUGGCGGUGGUGGGGAGGAGGGGUGCGCCAUGGCCUGGAGGGGAGUGUGUGUUGGGGUGUGUGUGUGGAGGUUCUUUUGAGUCACACACAAAGCAUUGUGCUGAGACACUGCAUUCCUGCUGGCUGGGCUUCCUGUUUCCAGAUGCAUUCCUGUCCCAGAGUCACCACAGAGACUGUUUGGAAUCCCGCCCCACAUUCUCCAAAUUCAGGGCGCGAUCUGGCAAAGGCUCCCUCCCCCACCCUCUUACUUUGGAGGGAGUCUGGGCUCCCUCCUACCCAGGGAGGGCUGGCAGGGCUCUGGCACGGCCGGGGUGUGAUUCCACACAUCUUCUUGGUCUUGCAUAAGGCAGUUCCUGGAGACCCAGCACUCUGGUUCUCUCUCUGCCUGUGAGAAGCGGAAUGGGUACUGUCUAGGAGGACUGGGCAGGGUGGGGGCAACCCAGAGGACCCAUGGCUAGCAGGGAAGGGCCUGGGCUUGAAUGUGACUCUGUUGAGACAUGGCCAGCAAUUCUGGCACUUGGCUGUCAUUCGGCUGGCCUGCGCAGAGAUUGGCUGUGGGCCUCAGUUUCCCCAUUUUAUAAAGUUUUAAAAUCUGA